AGCGGGGCGGUGAGGACAAGCCUGGGAGGGGCAGGCCCCCGGCCAGAAAUCUGGGCCUUUCGUGGUCAGAGGACACCGGCGGCCCCUUUGGGAUCCACCCCCAAUCACCACCACCUUGUUCUUCUCUGACCCUGGAUACUCUGGGUGUCCAUUUUUUGGAGCCCUGAGACCCUGUUUGAAGAGGGAUCCAUCUCAGCCCUGGUUGUGGGGCGAGGGUCUUGCUCAGCCUGCACCACCCUCCACCCUCCAGUAGGACCCAGAGGCAGCUGGGCUUUCCAUGGCCCUGGGCAGUGACGGGGUUCGGGUGACCAUGGAGAGUGCGCUCACCGCCCGUGACCGGGUGGGGGUGCAGGAUUUCGUGCUGCUGGAGAACUUCACCAGCGAGGCCGCCUUCAUCGAGAACCUGCGGCGGCGAUUUCGGGAGAAUCUCAUCUACACCUACAUUGGCCCCGUCCUGGUCUCUGUCAAUCCCUACCGGGACCUGCAGAUCUACAGCCGGCAGCAUAUGGAGCGUUACCGUGGCGUCAGCUUCUAUGAAGUGCCCCCUCACCUGUUUGCCGUGGCGGACACUGUGUACCGAGCACUGCGCACGGAGCGUCGGGACCAGGCUGUGAUGAUCUCUGGGGAGAGCGGGGCAGGCAAGACCGAGGCCACCAAGAGGCUGCUGCAGUUCUAUGCAGAGACCUGCCCAGCCCCCGAGCGCGGAGGUGCCGUGCGGGACCGGCUGCUACAGAGCAACCCGGUGCUGGAGGCCUUUGGAAAUGCCAAGACCCUCCGGAACGAUAACUCCAGCAGGUUCGGGAAGUACAUGGAUGUGCAGUUUGACUUCAAGGGUGCCCCCGUGGGUGGCCACAUCCUCAGUUACCUCCUGGAAAAGUCACGAGUGGUGCACCAGAAUCAUGGGGAGCGGAACUUCCACAUCUUCUACCAGCUGCUGGAGGGGGGCGAGGAGGAGACUCUUCGCAGGCUGGGCUUGGAACGGAACCCCCAGAGCUACCUGUACCUGGUGAAGGGCCAGUGUGCCAAAGUCUCCUCCAUCAACGACAAGAGUGACUGGAAGGUCGUCAGGAAGGCUCUGACAGUCAUUGAUUUCACCGAGGAUGAAGUGGAGGACCUGCUGAGCAUCGUGGCCAGCGUCCUUCAUUUGGGCAACAUCCACUUUGCUGCCAACGAGGAGAGCAAUGCCCAGGUCACCACCGAGAACCAGCUCAAGUAUCUGACCAGGCUCCUCAGCGUGGAAGGCUCGACGCUGCGAGAAGCCCUGACACACAGGAAGAUCAUCGCCAAGGGGGAGGAGCUCCUGAGCCCGCUGAACCUGGAGCAGGCCGCGUACGCACGAGACGCCCUCGCCAAGGCUGUGUACAGCCGCACUUUUACCUGGCUCGUCGGGAAGAUCAACAGGUCGCUGGCCUCCAAGGACGUGGAGAGCCCCAGCUGGCGGAGCACCACGGUUCUCGGGCUCCUGGAUAUUUAUGGCUUUGAAGUGUUUCAGCAUAACAGCUUUGAGCAGUUCUGCAUCAAUUACUGCAACGAGAAGCUGCAGCAGCUCUUCAUCGAGCUCACGCUCAAGUCGGAGCAGGAGGAGUACGAGGCAGAGGGCAUCGCGUGGGAGCCCGUCCAGUAUUUCAACAACAAAAUCAUCUGUGAUCUGGUGGAGGAGAAGUUUAAGGGCAUCAUCUCGAUUUUGGAUGAGGAGUGUCUGCGCCCCGGGGAGGCCACAGACCUGACCUUCCUGGAGAAGCUGGAGGAUACUGUCAAGCACCAUCCACACUUCCUGACGCACAAGCUGGCUGACCAGCGGACCAGGAAAUCUCUGGGCCGAGGGGAAUUCCGCCUUCUGCACUAUGCGGGGGAGGUGACCUACAGCGUGACCGGGUUUCUGGACAAAAACAAUGACCUUCUCUUCCGGAACCUUAAGGAGACCAUGUGUAGCUCAAAGAAUCCCAUUAUGAGCCAGUGCUUUGACCGGAGCGAGCUCAGUGACAAGAAGCGGCCAGAGACGGUCGCCACCCAGUUCAAGAUGAGCCUCCUGCAGCUGGUGGAGAUCCUGCAGUCUAAGGAGCCCGCCUACGUCCGCUGCAUCAAACCCAAUGAUGCCAAACAGCCCGGCCGCUUUGACGAGGUGCUGAUCCGCCACCAGGUGAAGUACCUGGGGCUGUUGGAAAACCUGCGCGUGCGCAGAGCCGGCUUUGCCUAUCGCCGCAAAUACGAAGCUUUCCUGCAAAGGUACAAGUCACUGUGCCCAGAGACGUGGCCCACGUGGGCAGGACGGCCGCAGGAUGGGGUGGCUGUGCUGGUCCGACACCUGGGCUACAAGCCAGAAGAGUACAAGAUGGGCAGGACCAAGAUCUUCAUCCGCUUCCCCAAGACCCUGUUUGCCACAGAGGAUGCCCUGGAGGUCCGGCGGCAGAGCCUGGCCACAAAGAUCCAAGCUGCCUGGAGGGGCUUUCACUGGCGGCAGAAAUUCCUCCGGGUGAAGAGAUCAGCCAUCUGCAUCCAGUCGUGGUGGCGUGGAACACUGGGCCGGAGGAAGGCAGCCAAGAGGAAGUGGGCGGCACAGACCAUCCGGCGGCUCAUCCGAGGCUUCGUCCUGCGCCACGCCCCCCGCUGCCCCGAGAACGCCUUCUUCCUGGACCAUGUGCGCACCUCUUUUUUGCUAAACCUGAGGCGGCAGCUGCCCCAGAAUGUCCUGGACACCUCGUGGCCCACGCCCCCACCUGCCCUGCGUGAGGCCUCAGAGCUUCUGCGGGAGUUGUGCAUAAAGAACAUGGUGUGGAAAUACUGCCGGAGUAUCAGCCCUGAGUGGAAGCAGCAGCUGCAGCAGAAGGCCGUGGCUAGUGAGAUCUUCAAGGGCAAGAAGGAUAAUUACCCUCAGAGUGUACCCAGGCUCUUCAUCAGCACUCGGCUUGGUACAGAUGAGAUCAGCCCCCGAGUGCUGCAGGCCUUGGGCUCUGAGCCCAUUCAGUAUGCGGUGCCUGUUGUGAAAUACGACCGCAAGGGCUACAAGCCUCGCUCCCGGCAGCUGCUGCUCACGCCCAACGCCGUCGUCAUCGUGGAGGACGCCAAAGUCAAGCAGAGGAUUGAUUACGCCAACCUGACCGGAAUCUCUGUCAGCAGCCUGAGCGACAGUCUUUUUGUGCUUCAUGUACAGCGUGCGGACAAUAAGCAAAAGGGAGAUGUGGUGCUGCAGAGUGACCACGUGAUUGAGACGCUGACCAAGACAGCCCUCAGUGCCAACCGCGUGAACAGCAUCAACAUCAACCAGGGCAGCAUCACGUUUGCAGGGGGCCCCGGCAGGGAUGGCACCAUUGACUUCACACCCGGCUCGGAGCUGCUCAUCACCAAGGCCAAGAACGGGCACCUGGCUGUGGUCGCCCCACGGCUGAAUUCUCGGUGAUAAAGGCGCCCACUGGACCCUCCCAACGCCCAAUGCUUUGCUUUUCUCCUCCUCCCCUUCCCAGUUACCAAAGACUCGAACUUCCAGACAGGGACCCAGGGACACCCCGAAGCCCACCUGCAAUCUCCCACCUCCUGCCCAUCCCUCUCUUGAGGGAGCAGCAGGGGCCAGGAGCUACCCCAGGAGUGGGCCAGGCCGGGCCACAGCAAUAGGAAAGCCAGGGCCAGAGCGAGCCAUGCCAGCCCUACUGCCGAUGCCAAAUAUUUGAGAGAAGGGAACUUUUGCUGAGGUUUUCUCUGAGGUUUUUUUGAUGCUUUAUAGGAAACUAUUUUUUAAAAAAAGCCAUUUCCCACCCAAGGACACAGUGGAUGUGUUUUCCCUGACUCCAGCAGGGCAAGGAAUGUAGCCGAGAGGUUGUGUGGGCUGGGCUCUGGUGCCCUCUUCCCUGGCCAGGACACCUCUCCUCCUGAUUCCCUUGGCACCUUGUCUUUCUGUCUGUUUACCUGUCUCCCUGCCUGCCCAUCUGCAUCUUUUGCAGCCCACUCUGACUUCCAUCUGGGGGCUGAGACCACCCUUGCCUGCCCCCUUCUUUCUGCCUUAAGAAUGUCCUUUUAGGCUGGGCAUGGUGGCUCACGCCUGUAACCCCAGCACUUUGGGAGGCGGAGACGGGCAGAUAACCUGAGGUCAGGAUUUCGAGACCAACCUGACCUACAUGGAGAAACUCCGCCUCUAGUAAAAAUACAAAAUUAGCCGGGCAUGGUGGUGCACGCCUCUAAUCCCAGCUACUCGGGAGGCUGAGGCAGGAGAAUCACUUGAACCCGGGAAGUGGAGGUUGCAGUGAGCCAAGAGUACACCACUGCACUCCAGCCUGGGCAACAGAGCGAGACUCCGUCUUAAAAAAAAAAAAAAAGAACGCCCUUUUACUGUCCUCAUCAUCCCAGUUUGAGGCAGUGCUGGAGUGGGGAAGGCCGUCUUAGACCAUAGAGGUUGGAAGACGCUGAGAGAUCAUCCAGCCCAGCCCCUUGAUGUUACAGAGCAGAAGACAGAUGCCCAAACAGGAGAAGGCACUUGCCCACGGUCAUACGGCAGGUUGCCACAAAACCAAGAUGGCAGCCCUUCCUCAGCGUGCCUCACUGCCACUCCCAGAGCCAGGGAGCCCCAUAAAACCCACAUCAUGUCUUAAGAGUAUAUCUGGCUCCUUGACCAGCAAUCGGCCCUGGGAGCCACCAGGUGGGAAAAGCGCCUCUGCCAGAGUCCAGGCCUUGGGAUGACAGACAGCUUGCCCGCACACUCGGGCCCCACUCAAGGAUGUAGGGCCUUUUCUGGCCCCUGACCCCUCCCUGGCAUGGGAGCGUGGGGACGGGGCUGGCCUUGGGAGGAGCGGCAGGGGCAUCACCUCCUUCUGCUGCUUCUCCCUGCUCCUACCCUCAAGGGCCUGGGGGCUGCCCAGCUGCCUCUAUGCCCUUCUGGGGGUCUCAGCCCACUGCUGACACUUCUGCAAUCCAGAGAAACACUAAAUAAAGCAAUACGUGUUUGCCAA